GCUUCGGGUUGGUGUCAUGGCAGCUGCGGGGAGCCGCAAGAGGCGCCUGGCGGAGCUGACGGUGGACGAGUUCCUAGCUUCGGGCUUUGACUCCGAGUCCGAAUCCGAGUCCGAAAAUUCUCCACAAGCGGAGACACGGGAAGCACGCGAGGCUGCCCGGAGUCCGGAUAAGCCGGGCGGGAGCCCCUCGGCCAGCCGGCGUAAAGGCCGUGCCUCUGAGCACAAAGACCAGCUCUCUCGGCUGAAGGACAGAGACCCCGAGUUCUACAAGUUCCUGCAGGAGAAUGACCAGAGCCUGCUAAACUUCAGCGACUCGGACAGCUCUGAGGAGGAAGAGGGGCCGUUCCACUCCCUGCCAGAUGUGCUGGAGGAAGCCAGUGAGGAGGAGGAUGGAGCGGAGGAAGGAGAAGAUGGGGACAGAGUCCCCAGAGGGCUGAAGGGGAAGAAGAAUUCUGUUCCUGUGACCGUCGCCAUGGUUGAGAGAUGGAAGCAGGCAGCAAAGCAACGCCUCACUCCAAAGCUGUUCCAUGAAGUGGUACAGGCGUUCCGAGCAGCUGUGGCCACCACCCGAGGGGACCAGGAAAGUGCUGAGGCCAACAAAUUCCAGGUCACGGACAGUGCUGCAUUCAAUGCUCUGGUUACCUUCUGCAUCAGAGACCUCAUUGGCUGUCUCCAGAAGCUGCUGUUUGGAAAGGUGGCAAAGGAUAGCAGCAGGAUGCUGCAGCCGUCCAGCAGCCCGCUCUGGGGGAAGCUUCGUGUGGACAUCAAGGCUUACCUGGGCUCGGCCAUACAGCUGGUGUCCUGUCUGUCGGAGACGACGGUGUUGGCGGCCGUGCUGCGGCACAUCAGCGUGCUGGUGCCCUGCUUCCUGACCUUCCCCAAGCAGUGCCGCAUGCUGCUCAAGAGAAUGGUGAUCGUAUGGAGCACUGGGGAAGAGUCUCUGCGGGUGCUGGCUUUCCUGGUCCUCAGCAGAGUCUGCCGGCACAAGAAGGACACUUUCCUUGGCCCCGUCCUCAAGCAAAUGUACAUCACGUAUGUGAGGAACUGCAAGUUCACCUCGCCUGGUGCCCUCCCCUUCAUCAGUUUCAUGCAGUGGACCUUGACGGAGCUGCUGGCCCUGGAGCCGGGUGUGGCCUACCAGCACGCCUUCCUCUACAUCCGCCAGCUCGCCAUACACCUGCGCAACGCCAUGACCACUCGCAAGAAGGAAACAUACCAGUCUGUGUACAACUGGCAGUAUGUGCACUGCCUCUUCCUGUGGUGCCGGGUCCUGAGCACUGCGGGCCCCAGCGAAGCCCUCCAGCCCUUGGUCUACCCCCUUGCCCAAGUCAUCAUUGGCUGUAUCAAGCUCAUCCCCACUGCCCGCUUCUACCCGCUGCGAAUGCACUGCAUCCGUGCCCUGACGCUGCUCUCGGGGAGCUCGGGGGCCUUCAUCCCGGUGCUGCCUUUCAUCCUGGAGAUGUUCCAGCAGGUCGACUUCAACAGGAAGCCAGGGCGCAUGAGCUCCAAGCCCAUCAACUUCUCCGUGAUCCUGAAGCUGUCCAAUGUCAACCUGCAGGAGAAGGCGUACCGGGACGGCCUGGUGGAGCAGCUGUACGACCUCACCCUGGAGUACCUGCACAGCCAGGCACACUGCAUCGGCUUCCCGGAGCUGGUGCUGCCUGUGGUCCUGCAGCUGAAGUCGUUCCUCCGGGAGUGCAAGGUGGCCAACUACUGCCGGCAGGUGCAGCAGCUGCUUGGGAAGGUUCAGGAGAACUCGGCAUACAUCUGCAGCCGCCGCCAGAGGGUUUCCUUCGGCGUCUCUGAGCAGCAGGCAGUGGAAGCCUGGGAGAAGCUGACCCGGGAAGAGGGGACACCCCUGACCUUGUACUACAGCCACUGGCGCAAGCUGCGUGACCGGGAGAUCCAGCUGGAGAUCAGUGGCAAAGAGCGGCUGGAAGACCUGAACUUCCCUGAGAUCAAACGAAGGAAGAUGGCUGACAGGAAGGAUGAGGACAGGAAGCAAUUUAAAGACCUCUUUGACCUGAACAGCUCUGAAGAGGACGACACCGAGGGAUUCUCGGAGAGAGGGAUACUGAGGCCCCUGAGCACUCGGCAUGGGGUGGAAGACGAUGAAGAGGACGAGGAGGAGGGCGAGGAGGACAGCAGCAACUCGGAGGAUGGAGACCCAGACGCAGAGGCGGGGCUGGCCCCUGGGGAGCUGCAGCAGCUGGCCCAGGGGCCGGAGGACGAGCUGGAGGAUCUGCAGCUCUCAGAGGACGACUGAGGCAGCCCAUCUGGGGGGCCUGUAGGGGCUGCCGGGCUGGUGGCCAGUGUUUCCACCUCCCUGGCAGUCAGGCCUAGAGGCUGGCGUCUGUGCAGUUGGGGGAGGCAGUAGACACGGGACAGGCUUUAUUAUUUAUUUUUCAGCAUGAAAGACCAAACGUAUCGAGAGCUGGGCUGGGCUGGGCUGGUGUGGCUGCUGAAGCCCCACAGCUGUGGGCUGCUGAAGUCAGCUCCGCGGGGGAGCUGACCCUGACGUCAGCAGACCGAGACCAGUCCCAGUUCCAGGGGGAGGCCUGCAGGCCCCUGGCCCCUUCCACCACCUCUGCCCUCCGUCUGCAGACCUCGUCCAUCUGCACCAGGCUCUGCCUUCACUCCCCCAAGUCUUUGAAAAUUUGUUCCUUUCCUUUGAAGUCACAUUUUCUUUUAAAAUUUUUUGUUUUGCAUCCGAAACCGAAAGAAAUAAAGCGGUGGGAGGCAGGGCCAUUGUGUUGA